UGGUGGCGUUGUGAUCCUGGAUGUGUCCAGGGAAGUCCUCUCCCCGUUUUCUUGGGCGGCUCCAGCCCAUCCAGCCCCCCUCAUCCUUCAUUGCCAUUUUCUCCUAUCAUUCCUUCAUAAAAACCUCAAAUAACAUCCUAACCUCGUUCCUAACAGCCUUAGCUGGAAGGGGACGAGGAGGCGGCUGCAAAGCGCUCCUCUCUGCUACUGGAAGCCCCUUCGUAUCUGGGGAGUCCCUGCCUUUUCCCAGAGCCUAUGCCUGUCUCUUGAGGGCUGUGGCCAUCCGCUUCUGCCACCCUUCACCGUUUGAGCGGCUGACUUUGAUAAGAACGAUCUGAAAUGAAGUUGUGUUUGAGGUGAGAUGAGACUGGACAGCUGGCGUUGGCACCAGACCUUGUCUUAGGUUUCAUCUCCUCCGACGUUGACCAAAGCCUUUGACUGCACUUGAUGCCCAGUUCUCGCUCCAUCCCUCUCCAUGAAAUGGCAUUGGGAAGUCCAGCAUUCAGAUAUUGUGUUAAAUCUCCCUUUAGAGACUGGCCUGGCUGCCAGUCCCGGCCUGCUGCUUAUUGGCUCUGAGGCACAGUAUAUUGUUGGCAGCCCCAACCCCCUACCACUCACUCUGAUACCGCUGUCCAUGAUCACUAAAGCACACACUAACUGGAAGUGUCUUGUUGCACAGUUUAUGGCCGGAAUGUCUUAAUUUUUCAUGACUGGGAUUUCAGUGUGUGUAGAUCUGUGUAUGCUUGUAUUUCUUUUAGACAUUUAAUGGAUAUUCUUGGUAAGAAGUGAAAAAACAUUAAGAAGAUUAGGAGCUAGGCAUUAUUGUUAACAGGUUUCCAAGUCAAGAAAUCAGCCAUGCUCCAGGUGGUUUUAGUAGCUAAGGAUAUAAAAUGGUAAUUAGAUUAAAAGACGGGUAUUCAAAAUGAGGCUUGAGAAGUGAACUCUUGUUCGUAUAUAGGAAGAAGAGGGGUAAGUGGGUAAGUUCAGUUGACCAUCACCUGACAGUAAGAUACAGAAUUGAGAUGUAUUGGUGGUGGUGGAUUUACCAGAAUAACACAGAUAUGCCUUUUAUGUCUUUCUUUCUUUUUCCCUUGUGGAACAGUAUAAUAAUUGUUUUUAUGGACAAUCUCAUUUGAACUUUUUUUGUCUGCCCCAAUAUGAGAAAUAUUCCAAAUUCUUGAUGUGUUUCCAGCCCUAGUAGGCUAGUCAUUUCCGGGAUGCUGUUGAGCCUGACAGGUCUGGCCUCAAUUAGGCAAUGGCUUACAUGGCAUGAAAGAGGACAUUAGUCAAACUGAUUUACAGCUUCAAGGUUCAGAAGUGUUUCUUAAGUUUGAGGGUGUGAAUACUAGUGAUGUACCUGGCAUUGAGAAAUUCCAAAAUUAAACUUGUAUUCAGCUCUAGCCUGCUUAAUCUCCUAUCAAACUAAGAUGGUACGUUUGUAAAUACAAAUGAAGUUAAUUGCAUUUUAAACUGAUCUGACUGGAAGGUUUUUGUUUAAUUUCUUAUACAGUGUCUGCCUGUUGAAUUUUAAAACACAUGUAUUUGAAGAGAUAGCAAAAUCUUUGUUAAGAGCUUAUUUGUAACUAUUGGAAUGAAUUUAUGUUUUUUUUUUGAGACGAGUCUUGCUCUGUUGCCCAGGCUGGAGUGCAGUGGCGCGAUCUCGGCUCACUGCAAGCCCCGCCUCCCGGGUUCACGCCAUUCUCCUGCCUCAGCCUCCCCAGCAGCUGGGACUAUAGGUGCCCGCCACCACGCCCGGCUAAUUUUUUUGUAUUUUUAGUAGAGACGGGGUUUCACCGUGUUAGCCGGGAUGGUCUGGAUCUCCUGACCUUGUGAUCUGCCCGCCUCGGCCUCCCAAAGUGCUGGGAUUACAGGCAUGAGCCACCGCGCCCGGCCGGCAUGAAUUUAUGUUUUACCAGUUUGCUUUAGAGGAAAAUUAAAGCAAAAGAGAGCAGCAAGUUGAUAAAAUUGUAUUUCUAAAUGUAAACCAGAAGCCCCCUUCUUUAAGCAUGGUCCAUUUAGUAAAUGUCAGACUUUAAUAUAGAAUUUAAGAUUACAAAAAAAGUUUAUGAAGCUUUUUUUUUUCUCGAGACAGAGUCUCGCUCUGUCGCCCAGGCUGGAGUGCAGUGGCGUGAUCUUGGCUCACUGCAACCUCCGCCUCCCGGGUUCAAGCCAUUCUCCUGCCUCAGCCUCCCGAGUAGCUGGGACUACAGGCGCAUGCCACCACUCCUGGCUUAUUUUUUGUAUUUUUAGUAGAGAUGGGGUUUCAUCAUGUUAGCCAGGAUGGUCUCAAACUCUCAACCACAGGUGAUCCACCAGCCUCGGCCUUCCAAAGUGCUGGGAUUACAGGUGAGCCACUGCGGCUGUCCCCAGAAUCUUUUGAUAGAGCUAAAAAUGUCUUGGAACCUCUUUUGGGCACUUGAAUAAUAUAAACAGUUGGUAAAACCUGCAUUCAUUGGUUUCAUCUACUUGUUUAUAUUGUAUAAAAUGAAUGGGGGAAAGGGUAGAUAGGAUUUGACAAACACACAUUAGUCCAGUGUGUGCAAAACAAGCUUGACAAAACUACAGAAAUACUUGCCUCCUUGGCUUUACUUAAAAUUAUUGAAUGCUAAAUAAUGCCUAGACACAGGUAGUAUUUAAAAAAAUAGGCAUAUAUUACCACAUACAAACAUGGAAUUGCAGGCAGUUUAUCUUGCAAAGCGGGGCCUUGGAAACGAAGUGUUAUGUUAAUGACAGAUAACACUUACUGGGCCUGAGUGGAAGGGCAGUCUAGUGACUUCAGUUACAUUUUAGAAGCACCUAGAAAUUAGGAAGAUUGGUUUUUGCACACUAUUUUAGCUAGACUGUUUGUCAGUUGUCUAAACCUUAACGUUUUCUAAAAGUGUACAUUUAAACACUGUUAGGGAGAUGUAUUACUGGUAGCUUUUAUUUUUUGGCUUGAAUCUAUCUUUCUUAAAUAUUUUGAGUAAAACACAAGGAAAGCCUUGACUCUUGUUUAUAUUGCGUGUGUUUUCUAAGGAAGUACACUUGUACUUCAUGGAUACUGGAAAUUUGAGCAGCACAUUCUUCAUCUCUUUAUUUCACCUCCUUGUUGCAUCUAAGUUUGUGGCUUGUGUAUUCUUAAAAACGUGUUUUAAAUGCUUGGAACACAGCAUUCAAAAACCGUUCGGUGAAAGAUGAGUUGCAUUUUAGAUCCUUUUAGAACUCUAAGACAUCUUAAAAAUCUUCACCAGUUUUUUAAUUCUUCUGUCUUAUCUGCUUCUCUGUCCUUCCUUUCAUCUUUCUGGAAACAGGAUUAUAAGGCGAUGUGUGUGUGUGUGUGUGUGUGUGUGUGUGUGUGUAAGAAUCGGCUGAAUUAAAAUGAUUCUUAACUUUUAAAUUGUAGUAAUAAAAUACAGUGGGUGAAUUUCUUCUAAUCCCUUUCUUUAAAAUCUGGCAUUUAUAUUGCUCUUAGUAGCUGAGUGAUGAACUAUAGUGUGUCAAAAAGUUAUGUUAUGGAUUCAUAUUUUAAAAUGUCCUUUUGCUCAUUAAUUCAGCAGAUUUUUACUGAAGGCUGGGUAUGAAUUAGGCACUAAGGAAAUGGAUAACCAAGACCCCUCUCUCUAGGAUCAUAUAGCUUGGGUCAGUGAUCUCCACUAAGUGUAUAUAGACAAUCCCCGACUUACAAUUUAACUUUACGAUGGUGCAGAAGCUAUAUGCGUUCAGUAGAAAUCAUAUUUCAGUAAAGUAUUAAUAUUUAGUAUUAAUAACCAUAGUAUUAAUAUUUCAGUACACUAAUAAAUUACAUGAGAUUUUCAAUGCAUUACUGUGUUAUUUUGUCCAACAGUAUGCUAAUGUAAGUGUUCUAAGCAUGUUUAAGGUAGGCUAAGUUAUGUUCAGUAAAUUUGGUGUAUUAAAUACAUUUUUGACUUAAUGAUAUUUUCAACUUAUGAUGGGUUUAUUGGGAGGUAAUCUCAUUGUAAGUUGUAUCAAAGAAUGUAAGCCUAUUCAUAGAGGAUGCGAAUAAAAUACUAGAAAUUCUGUUUAUAGUUCUAACUUGUGUAUGUUUAAUAAUGCACAUAAUAUGUUCAAAAGUAGUAUAUAUGCAUAUCAUUUAUAAAUGAUUAGCUUAUGGUAUAUUAAGUGCUGCAGUGCUAUAGGAGAAAGUGCUACGGAAAUACAGAGUGUGUAUGGGUGUCUCUGAUGGCCUAGAAGUGCUGCUAGCACUGUGCUCAUUUUAUAGUAUAUGCUCAAUAAUUGAGUGUUAAAGGAUUUAAUUUCCUAGUCACUUAUAGGUAGUUGUGUUUGCUAGUGGAAUAAUUAAGCAUGUAACAGUUGAUAAUUCAGUACUUUUCAUUUUGCUUAUCCACCAAAUCUAAGAUGCUUUAAAACAUUGACUCCCAACUAAGAUUUUGUUCACCAAUUUCUCAGUAUUAAUCUUAAAAUUUCGUUAGAUUUAUACUACCUAUGAUGUGAUGUUAGUUCGUUUAGCAUAAUGUAUCAUUCUAUACACGGAAAUUGAAUUUCACAGUCAGUACCUUCUGGGAUGCGUAUUUAUCUCCCUUAUUAAAGCACUUAUUUGCCUUCCUAUGAAUUUUUAAAAUUCACCAGUGAACUUUCUAGCAUUAGUUUGGAAUUGUUGGUUUCGGUUAAGCCUUUUAAAAGUAUACCAGAUCUUACUAUUUGUAAAGGAGAAAAAUGGGGCAGUUUUUAAGUAGUCUGCUUAUAUGUAGUCACCUGAGUGAUUACAAAGGUGCUGUUUUCACUAAUCUCACUGUUUCACUAAUUUCACUGUUUUCACCUCACUAAUCUUUAGUUCGUAGGUUUGGUGUGUCUCUGACAAGAGGAGAUAAAUAUAUUGAUGAACUCUGGAUUUUGGGGGAUGAGCAAAAUGAGGGGACAUCACUUGCUGGUUAGUGAGCUCCCCAUUUACCAAACUGGACAGCUCUUGUUUGUUUUUCCUUGUUCAUUGUCUCUCUUUGUGCUUAGUGAGACUUUACAGUGACAGCACUCAGGGUUGCCUUCCAGAAAGAUGUGUAAGGAAGUUAGAGUUGGGAUUGUGAUGCCCAACCCAUAGCCAGAUAUUUUCUCAGGACGAGAAAAGGAAGAUUUUUGGCACUGGAUUACAUGCUUGGAUCAUUGGAAAAGUUAGAGAAGUGAUUAUUAUUUUUGUUGUCACUAGAGAAAAAUCUGUUUUUGCAGCACCAGAGUAAUGCUGAGAGUUUGAAUUAGAAGCUUUAAUGUUAAACAGCUGCAGUGGUGGAGGGAUUUUUUUUUUUUUUUUUUUAAUUUAUGAACUAAAAAUUAGUAGUUGGAUAGUGUACUGAGAAGAUUAAGGUGGGACUGACAGUUCUUUUUAUACUGUAUCCGGGAAGCAUGGCUUCUCCUUUCAGAGCUUGUUUAUGCUUCUGCUUUUGCUUUUUGGGCCUCAUGACAUAUUUGUGUUUAAGUUGAGCAGUUUAAUGUCUUUCUGCAUUCCAAUAAGUCCUCUCAUUUAAUAAUAAAGAACUCUUGGAAGUUAGAGGUAUGUAGUUAAUUAUUGGCACAAAAGCCUGGUAAAAACUAGCUUUUCAAGUGUUUCCUUUAUUGUUCUUUCCGUUUGUUUCUUUUGUGUUGUGUGUGUGUGUGUGUGUUAUGCAGCAAUAGAAUAGAAUUUUCUUUUAUAGUCAGAGAUGUAUCCUAAGAUGUAUCUAUUCAAAGAUGACCAGAAUUCAAGACCUUUCCUUAACACCCCUCUUUAUUAGGGACUUAGUAUUCAUUAACAUAAGGCUCUUUUUAAUUUUUUUUAAUUAUCUUUUUCUUUUUUUUUUUUUGAGACAGAGUCUCUAUUGCUCAGGCUGGAGUGCAAGUGGCGUGAUCUUGGCUCACUGCAACCUCUGCCUCCCGGGUUCAAGCUAUUCUCAUGCGUCAGCCUUCCAAGUAGCUGGGAUUACAGGCACCCACCACCAUGCCCGGCUCAUUUUUGUAUUUUUAGUAGAGACAGGGUUUUACUAUGUUGGCCAGGCUGGUCUGGAAGUCCUGACCUCAAGUUAUCCACCUACGCUGGCCUCCCAAAGUGCUGAGAUUAUAGGCGUGAGCCACUGCUUCUGGCCUAUUUAUUUAUUUUUGAGACAGAGUCUUGCUCUGUCACCCAGGUUGGAGUGUAGUGGCGCAAUCUUGGCUCACUGCAACCUCUGUCUCCUGGUUCAAGCGAUUCUCUUGCCUCAGACUCCAAAGUAGCUGGGACUACAGGCGUGUGCCACCACACUGUCAUGCGCGUCCAUGUGAAGAGACCACCAAACAGACUUUGUGUGAGCAAUGAAGGUUUUUAAUCACCUGGGUGCAGGCGGGCUGAGUCCAAAAAGAAAGUCAGCGAAGGGAGAUAGGGAUGGGGCUGUUUUAUAGGAUUUGGGUGGGUAGUGGAAAAUUACAGUCAAAGGGGGUUUUUCUCUUGCAGGCAGGGGCGGGGGUCACGAGGUGCCCAGUGGGGGAGCUUCUGAGCCAGGAGAAGGAAUUUCACAAAGUUAAUCGCUCAGUUAAGGUGGGACAGGAAUAAAUCACAAUGGUGGAAUGUCAUCGGUUAAGGCAGGAACCUGCCAUUUUCACUUCUUUUGUGAUUCUUCAGUUGCUUCAGGCCAUCUGAAUGUAUUGUGCAGGUCACAGGGGAUGUGAUGGCUUAGCUUGGGCUCAGAGGCCUGACAACACCUGGCUAAUUUUUGUAUUUUGUAGUAGAGAUGGGGUUUCGCCGUGUUGUCCAGGCUGGUGUUGAACUCCUGGCCUUAAAUGAUCCACCCGCCUCCACCUCCCAAAAUGCUGGAAUUACAGGCGUGAGCCACCACGCCCAGCCAGGCUCUUUAUUUUAGGGAUUUUUUUUUUUUUUUGGACGGAGUUUUGCUCUUGUUGCCUAGGCUGGAGUGCAAUGGCACAGUCUCGGCUCACUGCAACCUCCGCCUCCCGAAUUCAAGCAAUUCUCCUGCCUCAGCCCUCCGAGUAGCUGGGAUUACAGGCACGGUGCCACCAUGCCCGACUAAUUUUGUAUUUUCAGUAGAGACGGAGUUUCUUCAUAUUGGUCAGGCUGUUCUCCAACUCCCGACCUCAGGUGAUCCGCCCGCCUCGGCCUCCCAAAGUGCUGGGAUUACAAGCAUGAGCCACCGUGCCUGGCCUAGGGCGGCGCUCAUCACUAUCUUGUGAAUAAGAUUCAGGAAAACUGAUGUUUUGAAACCUUGCCUAUAACAUGUUUGUUGGGGUACUAGACACUGGACCGCAUUAAAAGCAAAACUAUGCUAAAGUGGGAUUUUACAGAGGAAGUUGUCCAGUGUCUUUCAUUUCUGUAAAGAAGCUUGGUUGCCCCAGCAUCUUAUCCCUGUGGCAAAAGCCUUUUAACAUUUGCUAUGGUUGCCUUUUGGUGAUGACUCGUGAAAGGGUCUGGAGAGAUUACAUUAUGAAAAGGAUCUUUCUAACAAGAUAGGCCUCCACUAGUCUUUCCCAUGACAGCAAAUGGCAUCACUAUUGCAACACAAGUACUAAACUGAAAAAUCUAGACAUAUCCUCAGUUCCUCCCUUUCUCUCACUUUCUGACCAUAUCCCCUUAUCUCCAGUUAGAAUCUGUCACCAAGUUUUAUUAGUUUGGUAUUGAGUUUAGUCUGUUAGCUUCUGCUUAAUUGCCUCCACUUUAGUCCCCACUGCCAUCAUCUUUUGCUCCAAGACACUGUGCAGUAGUUUCCUAGUUUCACACAGUCAGUGUAUUCUUAAAAUCCAAACCAGAUCUUGUUAUUCCUUUCUUUAAAGUCUAUAAUUAAUUUUUAAAAAUGUAGUCUUUAUAGUGGUCUACAAGGCUGUAAAUAAUUUGGUUCCUGCUUAAAACUCCAACCUCAAUUGUAGUAAUUUACCCCUUGCCUCCUGUACACUAGCUACACUAGCCAUCUUCUUGUUCUUGGAACCUAUUCUGGCUUGCAGCCUUUGCAUUUGCUACUUUCUCUCAUCCUGGAAAGACUAUUUAUGAAUUUUUACAUGUCUGGCUCAUUCUCAUAUCUGAUGGCCACAGCUCAGAUGGCCUCAAGGACGCCUUCCUUUAUCACCUCAUAUGAAGUGGUAUUUGUCUAUCACUAUUGUGCAAUAUUCUGAACAGUUUGUGUACAGCCUUUAUCAUAAUACGUAAUUAUCACGUUUAUUGUCAGGUCUGUUGCUGAAUCCCCAGUGUCAGGAUAGGUGCAGUGCCUAAUGUAUUUUAAGUGCUCAGUAAAUAUUGGAUGUCUGGAUGAAUGUAUAAAUGUAUAAAUAAUGGAGAGAAGUUGUGGAGAGCUUUCAUGUUUGUCAGAUCGGGGGGUAAAAAAUAAAGACAGGAAUCGAGUUAUACUAUAUGUAUCCACCUCAAAAUUUCUUUUCCUUUCAGCAGCUUUUAAAAAGUUUGUGCUUAAAGUUUUUUUUUUUUUUUUUUGGGACGAUGUCUGUCGCUUCCCAGGCUGGAGUGCGACCUUGGGAUCACUGCAACCUCUACCUCCUGGGUUGAGGCGAUUCUCCUGCUUCAGCCUCCUGAGUAGCUAGGACUACAGGCACAAGCCACCACGCCCAGCUAAUUUUUGUAUUUUUAAUAUAGACGGGGUUUCAGCAUGUUGGCCAGGAUGGUCUUCAUUUCUUGACCUCGUGAUCCACCUGCCUCGGCCUCCCAAAGUGCUGGGAUUACAGGAGUGAACCACCGCGCCCGGCCUGUGCUUAAAGUUUUAAAUGAUAGUUAAAAAUAAAUAGUCCUAAAUAUAGUAUGUAGUUUUGUCUGUUUAGUUCAAAUAUUUGAAGCUGAUAAAUAAAUUCCUGUGAGAUUAGUAUGGGGUAAGUAUUGUACUUAUGAACACUUGAGAAUGUCUUUUGGUUAUGUAUAAAAUUUAAUAAUUUUAUUCCUGAAAUAAUCAUUUUUAUAUGAUGACCUUCAUGUACUUUUCAUUUAUGAUGACAAGUAUUAUCCUACUGCCAUAUAUGAAGUUAGAGUUAGAAAGUUAUUUGCUUAAAGUGUUAUACAGAGUUAUAUAAAAUUCAACACACAGAGCUCUCUCUUGGUUCUAAAUAAUCCAGGUGAUUUUAAAUUAAAUUUUAUGAUUAACUUUUUUUUUCUUGGUCUAAGACUCUUUUUCUCUUAUAUUCCAUGGCUAAUGCUUCCCUCCCUCUUUUCUUAGUCUUUUGUUUUUGUUUUUAUUACAAUGGUAUAUGCACAUAGUUUAGAAUCAGAUGGGAAUACAGGGCUUGUUAUGAAAAUGGUACUGUUAGCUGGGCAUGGUGGUUCAGGUCUCCCGAAUUGUGGGGACUACAGGUGUGCACCACCACACCUGGCUAAUUUUUUUAAAUUUUGCAGAGACGAAGCCUCACUGUGUUGCUGGUCUGAAACUCCUGGCCUCAAGCCUCAGCCUCCCAAAGCACUGGGAUCAUAGGCAUGAGCCACUGUGCUGGCUGGCGGAGGCCUCUGAGAGAACUUGACAUCUGGGCUUAGUUUUGACAGAUAAGGAUCUGGCAAGGCAGGUAGUUCGAGGGGAAAGAUACAUGGCAGUUUGCCGGUGAGCUUAUCUCACUAUGCCAGCCUCUGGAAAUAGAAAUCAUACACUGGCCCUAAUUUCAAGACACUAAAUCUUGUCAGGGUUUUGCUUCACAGAGAAGAUGCAUAAAAUUUGGUCUUAAAAAUGAGUUCACCAUGCACACAUACACACAAAAAAAGUAAAUAUUGCAUUACUGUAUAUAUGAGGUUCCAAAAUAGGCAAAACUAAUUUAUGGUGACAGAAUAGUGGUGACCUCUGAGGGUCGGUAUCGACUGGGAGAGAACAGGAGAGAGCCUACUGGGGUGCUGGAAAUGUUCUGUAUCUUAAUUUUGCAGGAUAAUUCCUUGGAUGCAUCCCUAAAAAUUCAGUCAAGCUAUAUAGUAAGAUUUGUACAGUUUACGUAAGUAAUAGGAGAGAUAAGAGGGGGAACCUGUGGAAAUGCAGAACAUUUCAAGAUCUAGAAAGCAACAUUUGCAAGGGUACACAGUGUUCAGACAGGGACCAAAUCAUAGAAACUACUAGGGCUUGCCAUGCUGAAACGACUGACUUCAAACCAUAGGGCAUACGUACCUUCCACUGAAGAAGAGCACCUGAGUAAAAUGACUAGAGGUGCAUUUCAAAGAUUAUUCUAUUGGAAAUACAAAGAAUGAAUUGGAGGAGUAGGAGGCAAAUAGUCCAAGGGACAGAUAAAAACCUUUUUUUUUUUUUUUUGAGACAGGGUCUCCCUCUGUCACCCUAGCUGGAGUGCAGUUGUGCGAUCAUGGCUCACUGCAGCCUCUACUUCCUGCGCUCAUGCAAUCCUUCCAUCUCAGCCUCCCAAGUGUCUGGGACUCCAGAUGUGUGGACCACACCUGGCUAAUUUUUUUAUUUUGUUGUAGUGACGGGAAUCUCACUGUUGUUUCCCAGGCUGGUCUUGAACUCCUGAACUCAGGCAAUCUUCUGGCCUUGACCUCUCAAAGUGCUGGGAUUACAGGUGUGGGCUACAGUGCCUGGCCUUAUUAAAAUGUUGACGUAAUAAAUGGGACUACCUAGUGCUGCUGUGCUUUCUCCUUAAAGGAGAAAGCUGACAGAAUACAACUAGCAGCAGUAAUCUGGUAAAUUGUGCUUUCUAGAGUAAAUUUUGUCUCAUGACAUUUAUGCAAAUAUUCAAAUGUUUCAGGAAUAUAAACAUUUAAAAUUUGGGUUAUAAAUAAUGCCUCCUGGCUCUGAAAUUAUCUGAAUUCAUGAAGCAAUCAGUAGUAAAUAUGAAGGAAAAAUGAAACACAGCCUUAUAUGCAAGGACAAGCACAAAUUUCUAAUUCUUAUUAUAAUUUGGGUGCCCACCUGGUUUUGAAGGUGAGCCUUGGUUUGACUGGUUCUGAGACAUUUCUCUCAAAUAGCAAAUGAGUAGUGGGUAUGAAUAGGGUACAUUGGAAAGUCAUGUCAAAAUUCCAUGCAAUUUUAGGAGCUUUUUUUCUCCCAUGUAAUUUAUAUAAUUUGACAUGUGUAUUCCUAUGUAAAAUAUUUAACCACUUCUCUACAAUAAGCAUUAAGUGGGCUAAUUAUUAUGCUCUUCUUAUUUCAUAUUUCUGUGAUUUCUCUUAUCUGGAAUGACUUUUUUAUGCCACCCAGGCUGGAGUGCAGUGGCACAUUUACUGCUCACUGCAGCCUCAACUCCCCAGGGUCAAGCCAUCCUCCUAUUUCAGCUUCCCUAGCAGCUGGGACUACAGGUGUGCACCACUAUGCCCUGCUAAUUUUUGUGUUUUUUUGUAGAGACGGGGUUUUGCUAUGUUGCCCCGGCUGGUCUUGAACUCCUGAGCUCAAGAGAUCCACCCACCACAGCCUCCCAAAGUGUUGGGAUUACAGGCGUGAGCCACUGCACCUAGCUUCUUUUCUAAUUUGUUUUUAUUCUGAGAUCAGAUGAGAUUGGCAUGUUCAGGUUGGUAUGGCCAUAGACUGCUUUUAUCUAUUCUAAUAAUUUUGUAUUGUACAAUGUGUUGGAAAGGCAAGAUGAAGUUAGAUUAUGAAGGGUUCAUUUCCAUUCAAUUCUGUCUAUCCUUCUGGACUUUGCCUAAAUCUUACCUUCUUUGGAGCUUUCCUGAACUUACUUAUCUCCUUUGAAUUCUUACAUUUGGAUCCUUUGUAUUUGAGUAUUUUUACAUAUAUAUGUACAUAAAUAACACAUGUUUUAUGUGUAUUAAUUUACUCUCCCAACUAGAUUGAAAGCUGCUGAAGAGUAACCUUUUUUUAAAACCACAUUGGACUGUUUUAAGCACAAAUUUAGCAUAUGCUUGAUGAUUGAGAGAACCAUAUGGUUACAGUCAUUGGUGUGUCUGUAUGAUUGUGAUAUGUUGCUAUUUAAAAAUCAAUAGUUAUUUCUUAUUUAGUUUUCUGUUAAGCCAUAACCUUUUGCUCUCAUUUAUACGUCUUCUGAACGUUAAGUAACAUGUGGCUCAUAUUUCAAACUCCCAAUUUGGAAUUUUAUAGCAAUGUGACUGAAGUUUAUAAUUACAGGUCUCAGAGGACUGCACUACACAGAAGUUCUCUAUGUGUUAGAAGAAUUUAUUAGAAGAUAGACAAUUGUAGGUUACACUGUAAUUUAGAAGACUUUUGCGCAUCUCAUGUAUUUGUGUCAGUUUGAGAAUUUGAAAAUGCCCCCAAAAUGUCUGUUCUUCACUAGUGCCUCUUGUGAUCCUGGCAGAGAUAAGCUAAACUUUUGAAAGGGUAGACUUUUUCUGUUUAUCUUAGUAUCCUGAGUCCCUAAAUCUGGAAUGUAGUAGAUGUUUGUGCAUUUCCCUAUGUCAGUGAAGUCAAAAUACUACAGGUGGAUUUUUCAGCUUUUCAAAGUUUUCACAUUUACUAAGUCCUUCACAGUUAUCUCCUACUAGUUAAAAAACUAUUUGCCUCAAUUUAUGCCAGUGCUACUUUGACAUUUGCAUUGCUGUAAAACCCUUACUAAAAGGUAUGUUUUUCUAGUAUACAAAUACAUGUAUGCAGCUUUUCUCAUAUCUUUGAGAAAGCAAAAAAUUGUACUAAAUUAUGAUUUUGACUGCAAUAGGAUUAUGGCUUAGUCAUGAUCAGUAUUAUAUUUUCAACUAUGUCUUACUAGGAUUAUUGUAAAAGACUUUCAAAAUAGUUCAUGUGAAUUUUUGUCUGAUCUUCACAAACUCAGGUAUGUACAUAGCUCUCCCCCACCUUCUCCUGGCUUUGCCAAUUUAUUUUAUUUUUAUUGUGAAUAUAUAUAUAUAUAGAACAUACCAUUUACCAUUUGAACUAUUUUAAAAAAUGUACAAUUAGUGGCAUGAAGUACAUUCACAAUAUUGUAUAACCAUCACCACUAUCCAUUUCCAGAACUUGUUCAUCAUCCCAAACAGAAAUUCUCUAUCCCUUUUUUUCCCCAGCCCCUGGUAACCUCUAUUCUACUUUCUGUUUUUAUGAAUUUGCCUAUUCUAGAUACUUCAUGUAAAUAGAAUCGUACAAUAUUUGACCUUUCUUAUUUCACUUAGGAUAAUGUUUUCAAGGUUUAUCCAUGUUGUAGUACAUAGCAGAAUUUAAUUUCUUUUUUUGACUGAAUAAUUUGUAUAUACUACAUCUUGUUUGUACAUCCAUCUGUUGAUGGGACAUAUUUGAGUUGUUUCCACCUUUUGGCUAUUGUGAAUAAUGUUGUUGUGAACAUUGGUGUACAAAUAUCUGUCUGAGUCCUGCUUUCACUUCUUUUGGAUAUAAACCUAGGAAUGGAAUUGCUGGGUCAUAUGGUAAUUCUAUAUUUAACCCUUUAAGGAACAGCUAAACUGGUUUCCACAGCUUCUGUACCGUUUUAUAUUUCCACCAGCAAUGCACAAGUGCUCCUUCCAUUUUCUCCAUAUCUACCCAAUACUUGUUAUUUUGUUUUCUUUCAAUUAAUAACCAUCCUAAUGGGUGUGACAUAGUAUUGUCAUUUUGAUUUUUAGUUUCCUAAUGGCUAGUGCUAAUGAGCAUUUUUUUAAUGUGCUAUUGGUCAUUUGUAUGUCUUUUUUGGAGACAUGUCUAUUCAAUCCUUUGCCCAUUUUUGAAUUGAGAUGUGUGCUUUUUUGUUGUUGAGUUGUAGUUCUGUAGUUCUUUAUACAUUCUGGAUAUUAUUCUCACAUCAGAUAUAUGAUUUACAAAUAUUUUCUCCCAAAUAUUUCUGUGGGUUACAGAUAUAUUAAUAUCUGUGGAUUGUCUUUCAUGGUCUUGAUAGGAUCUUUUAAUGCCCAAAAGUUUUUAAUUUUGAUGAAAUAAUGUAUGUAGUUUUGAACUUAAACAAUGUUACAGAUUGUGCAAAGGGUAUAACCAUGAAAUUCUGAUAGAGUGACCCCACAGCUGCAGAAAACCAGAAUAGAAAGAACCCUACUCUAAAACCCAAAAGACUUCCCUAGAUAGAGUCCUUUGAAAAUAAUUUUCUAAAUUAUUCACACAGCCUGUGGAUAAAUUAAGAGGAAAUGAUAUCUGUAACAGUGCUGCUUGUGAUGAAAACACGGAAGAGUCAAUUAUAUUAUCAAAUCUUAGCUGGAAUGGAAAAUCAGGAGGAUAUUUAUUAGCAAACAUUAAUAAAAGGUUGGCCUUUAUUAUUGUAAGCAUGUACACAGACGACAGCAGGUAGUCUCUACCAUAAGAAUGAGAAAUGCCUCCUAUCUUUAUGAAUUCUGAAAUUUAACCUUUCUUAGCCCAAUUGCUGUAAGGGCCUAGGGUUUAUUUGUUAUGUGUGUUAUUGGAGUAGAGACUGUUCGAAGGUUAAGUGGGUAUUUAGUGAUGCAAGUGACAUUUAUAUGUUUUAAAAUCUUCUGCUUUUGUAGGCACUUUUAAAAAUGAAAUGCUAUAUUUUUAAACUUUUAAAAAUUAUUUUUUAUUAUUUUUUGCAGAGAUGAGGUCUUGCUGUGUUGCCCAGGCUGGUCUCAAACUCUUGGCCUCAAGAGAUCCUCCUGCCUUGGCCUCCCAAAGUGCUGGGAUUACAGACGUGAACCACGUGCCUGGCCCAAACUUUUUAAAGACUUUAUUUCUGGAGGCAGGUUCUCAGAAGAUAUCCUAUCUUAAUGGGCAUAUAUAUAGAGAGAGUAGUAGUUACAGAUGUAGAGCUAAAACGACUGAAGGAUGCUUUCAAGAGGACCUGUGGACUCUCAUAUUACAUGGGCCAGCACUGCUUCAUCCGGGAAGUGCUUGGGGAUGGAGUGCCUCCAAAGGUUGCUGAGGUGAUUUACUGUUCUUUUGGUGGAACAUCCAAAGGGCUGCACUUCAAUAAUUUAAUAGUUGGACUUGUCCUCCUUACAAGAGGCAAAGAUGAAGAGAAAGCAAAAUACAUUUUUAGUCUUUUUUCAAGUGAAUCUGGGAACUAUGUUAUACGGGAAGAAAUGGAAAGAAUGCUCCACGUGGUGGAUGGUAAAGUCCCAGAUACACUCAGGAAGUGUUUCUCAGAGGGUGAAAAGGUAAACUAUGAAAAGUUUAGAAAUUGGCUUUUUCUAAACAAAGAUGCUUUUACUUUCUCUCGAUGGCUUCUAUCUGGAGGUGUGUAUGUUACCCUCACUGAUGAUAGUGAUACUCCUACUUUCUACCAAACUCUGGCUGGAGUCACACAUUUGGAGGAAUCAGACAUCAUUGAUCUUGAGAAACGCUAUUGGUUAUUGAAGGCUCAAUCCCGGACUGGACGAUUUGAUUUAGAGACAUUUGGCCCAUUGGUUUCACCACCUAUUCGUCCAUCUCUAAGUGAAGGUUUGUUUAAUGCUUUUGAUGAAAAUCGUGACAAUCACAUAGAUUUUAAGGAGAUAUCCUGUGGGUUAUCAGCCUGUUGCAGGGGACCCCUGGCUGAAAGACAAAAAUUUUGCUUCAAGGUAUUUGAUGUUGACCGUGAUGGAGUUCUCUCCAGGGUUGAACUGAGAGACAUGGUGGUUGCACUUUUAGAAGUCUGGAAGGACAACCGCACUGAUGAUAUUCCUGAAUUACAUAUGGAUCUCUCUGAUAUUGUAGAAGGCAUACUGAAUGCACAUGACACCACAAAGAUGGGUCAUCUUACUCUGGAAGACUAUCAGAUCUGGAGUGUGAAAAAUGUUCUUGCCAAUGAGUUUUUGAACCUCCUUUUCCAGGUGUGUCACAUAGUUCUGGGGUUAAGACCAGCUACUCCGGAAGAAGAAGGACAAAUUAUUAGAGGAUGGUUAGAACGAGAGAGCAGGUAUGGUCUGCAAGCAGGACACAACUGGUUUAUCAUCUCCAUGCAGUGGUGGCAACAGUGGAAAGAAUAUGUCAAAUACGAUGCCAACCCUGUGGUAAUUGAGCCAUCAUCUGUUUUGAAUGGAGGAAAAUACUCAUUUGGAACUGCAGCCCAUCCUAUGGAGCAGGUCGAAGAUAGAAUUGGAAGCAGCCUCAGUUACGUGAAUACUACAGAAGAGAAAUUUUCAGACAACAUUUCUACUGCAUCUGAAGCCUCAGAAACUGCUGGCAGCGGCUUUCUGUAUUCUGCCACACCAGGGGCAGAUGUUUGCUUUGCUCGACAACAUAACACUUCUGACAAUAACAACCAGUGUUUGCUGGGAGCCAAUGGGAAUAUUUUGUUGCACCUUAACCCUCAGAAACCAGGGGCUAUUGAUAAUCAGCCAUUAGUAACUCAAGAACCAGUAAAGGCUACAUCAUUAACACUAGAAGGAGGACGAUUAAAACGAACUCCACAGCUGAUUCAUGGAAGAGACUAUGAAAUGGUCCCAGAACCUGUGUGGAGAGCACUUUAUCACUGGUAUGGAGCAAACCUGGCCUUACCUAGACCAGUUAUCAAGAACAGCAAGACAGACAUCCCAGAGCUGGAAUUAUUUCCCCGCUAUCUUCUCUUCCUGAGACAGCAGCCUGCCACUCGGACACAGCAGUCUAACAUCUGGGUGAAUAUGGGUAUGAUGAGCCUGAGAAUGUUUCCUCAGCAUUUACCGAGAGGAAAUGUACCUUCUCCGAAUGCACCUUUAAAGCGGGUAUUAGCCUAUACAGGCUGUUUUAGUCGAAUGCAGACCAUCAAGGAAAUUCACGAAUAUCUAUCUCAAAGGCUGCGCAUUAAAGAGGAAGAUAUGCGCCUGUGGCUAUACAACAGUGAGAACUACCUUACUCUUCUGGAUGAUGAGGAUCAUAAAUUGGAAUAUUUGAAAAUCCAGGAUGAACAACACCUGGUAAUUGAAGUUCGCAACAAAGAUAUGAGUUGGCCUGAGGAGAUGUCUUUUAUAGCAAAUAGUAGUAAAAUAGAUAGACACAAGGUUCCCACAGAAAAGGGAGCCACAGGUCUAAGCAAUCUGGGAAACACAUGCUUCAUGAACUCAAGCAUCCAGUGUGUUAGUAACACACAGCCACUGACACAGUAUUUUAUCUCAGGGAGACAUCUUUAUGAACUCAACAGGACAAAUCCCAUUGGUAUGAAGGGGCAUAUGGCUAAAUGCUAUGGUGAUUUAGUGCAGGAACUUUGGAGUGGAACUCAGAAGAAUGUUGCCCCAUUAAAGCUUCGGUGGACCAUAGCAAAAUAUGCUCCCAGGUUUAAUGGGUUUCAGCAACAGGACUCCCAAGAACUUCUGGCUUUUCUCUUGGAUGGUCUUCAUGAAGAUCUUAAUCGAGUCCAUGAAAAGCCAUAUGUGGAACUGAAGGACAGUGAUGGGCGACCAGACUGGGAAGUAGCUGCAGAGGCCUGGGACAACCAUCUAAGAAGAAAUAGAUCAAUUGUUGUGGAUUUGUUCCAUGGGCAGCUAAGAUCUCAAGUAAAAUGCAAGACAUGUGGGCAUAUAAGUGUCCGAUUUGACCCUUUCAAUUUUUUGUCUUUGCCACUACCAAUGGACAGUUAUAUGCACUUAGAAAUAACAGUGAUUAAGUUAGAUGGUACUACCCCUGUACGGUAUGGACUAAGACUGAAUAUGGAUGAAAAGUACACAGGUUUAAAAAAACAGCUGAGUGAUCUCUGUGGACUUAAUUCAGAACAAAUCCUUCUAGCAGAAGUACAUGGUUCCAACAUAAAGAACUUUCCUCAGGACAACCAAAAAGUACGACUCUCAGUGAGUGGAUUUUUGUGUGCAUUUGAAAUUCCUGUCCCUGUGUCUCCAAUUUCAGCUUCUAGUCCAACACAGACAGAUUUCUCCUCUUCGCCAUCUACAAAUGAAAUGUUCACCCUAACUACCAAUGGGGACCUACCCCGACCAAUAUUCAUCCCCAAUGGAAUGCCAAACACUGUUGUGCCAUGUGGAACUGAGAAGAACUUCACAAAUGGAAUGGUUAAUGGUCACAUGCCAUCUCUUCCUGACAGCCCCUUUACAGGUUACAUCAUUGCAGUCCACCGAAAAAUGAUGAGGACAGAACUGUAUUUCCUGUCAUCUCAGAAGAAUCGCCCCAGCCUCUUUGGAAUGCCAUUGAUUGUUCCAUGUACUGUGCAUACCCGGAAGAAAGACCUAUAUGAUGCGGUUUGGAUUCAAGUAUCCCGGUUAGCGAGCCCACUCCCACCUCAGGAAGCUAGUAAUCAUGCCCAGGAUUGUGACGACAGUAUGGGCUAUCAAUAUCCAUUCACUCUACGAGUUGUGCAGAAAGAUGGGAACUCCUGUGCUUGGUGCCCAUGGUAUAGAUUUUGCAGAGGCUGUAAAAUUGAUUGUGGGGAAGACAGAGCUUUCAUUGGAAAUGCCUAUAUCGCUGUGGAUUGGGAUCCCACAGCCCUUCACCUUCGCUAUCAAACAUCCCAGGAAAGGGUUGUAGAUGAGCAUGAGAGUGUGGAGCAGAGUCGGCGAGCGCAAGCCGAGCCCAUCAACCUGGACAGCUGUCUCCGUGCUUUCACCAGUGAGGAAGAGCUAGGGGAAAAUGAGAUGUACUACUGUUCCAAGUGUAAGACCCACUGCUUAGCAACAAAGAAGCUGGAUCUCUGGAGGCUUCCACCCAUCCUGAUUAUUCACCUUAAGCGAUUUCAAUUUGUAAAUGGUCGGUGGAUAAAAUCACAGAAAAUUGUCAAAUUUCCUCGGGAAAGUUUUGAUCCAAGUGCUUUUUUGGUACCAAGAGACCCGGCUCUCUGCCAGCAUAAACCACUCACACCCCAGGGGGAUGAGCUCUCUGAGCCCAGGAUUCUGGCAAGGGAGGUGAAGAAAGUGGAUGCGCAGAGUUCGGCUGGGGAAGAGGACGUGCUCCUGAGCAAAAGCCCAUCCUCACUCAGCGCUAACAUCAUCAGCAGCCCGAAAGGUUCUCCUUCUUCAUCAAGAAAAAGUGGAACCAGCUGUCCCUCCAGCAAAAACAGCAGCCCUAAUAGCAGCCCACGGACUUUGGGGAGGAGCAAAGGGAGGCUCCGGCUGCCCCAGAUUGGCAGCAAAAAUAAACUGUCAAGUAGUAAAGAGAACUUGGAUGCCAGCAAAGAAAAUGGGGCUGGGCAGAUAUGUGAGCUGGCUGACGCCUUGAGUCGAGGGCAUGUGCUGGGGGGCAGCCAACCAGAGUUGGUCACUCCUCAGGACCAUGAGGUAGCUUUGGCCAAUGGAUUCCUUUAUGAGCAUGAAGCAUGUGGCAAUGGCUACAGCAAUGGUCAGCUUGGAAACCACAGUGAAGAAGACAGCACUGAUGACCAAAGAGAAGAUACUCGUAUUAAGCCUAUUUAUAAUCUAUAUGCAAUUUCGUGCCAUUCAGGAAUUCUGGGUGGGGGCCAUUACGUCACUUAUGCCAAAAACCCAAACUGCAAGUGGUACUGUUACAAUGACAGCAGCUGUAAGGAACUUCACCCGGAUGAAAUUGACACCGACUCUGCCUACAUUCUUUUCUAUGAGCAGCAGGGGAUAGACUAUGCACAAUUUCUGCCAAAGACUGAUGGCAAAAAGAUGGCAGACACAAGCAGUAUGGAUGAAGACUUUGAGUCUGAUUACAAAAAGUACUGUGUGUUACAGUAAAGCUACCACUCUGGCUGCUAGACAGCUUGGCGGUGAGGGAGAUGACUCCUUGUAGCUGACAUUUGGCAAAAGCGUCACUGAAAGGCAAGCUAAAUGUAGUUAUUUUAUCCUGUGGCCCUGAAGCACAAAAUAAAAAUUCUAAUUAAAAUAGUUAACUUUAAGAGUAGUAAUCAUUUUAUUUUGAAGUCUCAUACAAGCUCUCCGAUAGAGAACUUUCAGGCAGAUCCCACCAUUAGCCUGUAAACAAAAGGUUUGGCACCAGCCACCUGGGACCAAAUAAGAAUUCAAUUGUGCUUGUCCAGAUAUGAACAAAUAUGUAGUGAGUAUAGAGUUUACCAUAAUCAUAACAAAUAUUAAAGAUUUCCUUGGAGUCAGAGUAAAAAACAAACAAUUAUAAUGUUGUCUAGGGACGACAUGAUAUGCUACCUCCUUUUUCCUGAAGUUUUAUUCCAUUAUAUUGACAAGAUGGAGAAAGCAAGAUCACGAAGGUGUGCAAAUGAUUCUUAAGGCAUGGACGAGGAUUUUUCAAUUUAUUUUUUAAACUGUUUCCAUACCCUUUCUUUGUCUUUCUUGCUUUUUGUUUUUGCCGUUGUAUUUAUGUUUGAGACACAACCAGUCAUUGGUGGCAGGGGCAUAUAGUGGUCAGUCUGAAAGGGAGGCUCUCUUAAGAGCUGUGUGCCUUCCACCCAGAGCCUUGUGGGAGACCCAGUAGAAAGAAACAGCAUCCUGGGAAAUCCAGCUACCAUGGCCCUCCCAGUGGAGGCAUCUUACAUUUAGGAUACUUCAAGUAUCCUCAGAAAUGUAUUCUGCACCCCCGGCCCCACCCAUGCUGAGGGAAGGGGAGCAGUUGCCAAUAUUUGCACCAUCUUCACAUGCACCUGUUGCAACAAGAGCUUCUGGGAAGGUAAGUGGCAUUGGAGCUAGAUCACGUUUCACAAUUAGUGGUUGUUCUUUUCUGUGUUUGUCUUGCACUUUAAAAAAGAGAGAACACAUGCAAAUGAACUUGCUUGUGUGUAUUUGAUGGCUCUAAGGGCUAUAAAUUACAAACAAAACACAUCCCAGACAUUAGGAGUUCAUAAGUGUAUUUAAUGAAAUUGGUGGUUUUAGGAAGUCAACUUUAGUUUUGCUUUGUUUGCAUGUCCACUAAUUUUUUUAUUUUGAUAUUUGUCUUUUUUUUAAAUUUUACAGUAGUCAUCGAAAGUUAUGUUUCUUUGCUUACUUCAUUUUUUUCUCUAAUCAAGACUGGAACAAAAGUAUAAAUAUUAUUUAUUUCAGGUAGCAUUUUUUUCGUGUAGUUUUUUAAUAUAUACUUGAAGGAAAUGUUUCACCUUAUUUUUGGUCUUUGUUUAUUCAUUUAGACCCUGCAAGUUGAUUCUCAUUAAUUGUCAGAUUCCACUACCCUUUCUUCCUCAUAGAUAGUAAUUACCAAUGUAACUAAGUAUUUGUGUUCUGAUAUCUGAGGCCAGUAACUAUUAAUAUCUAGUUCUCAGAGCAUUUGGAAAGGUUAUCUUAAAUGGCUACCUAAAUUGAAAUCCUUUUCAGAAAAAAUAUAAUUGCAAGUAGGUAGGACUGGCCUAAAUUGUCUAAUGUAAUAAAGUCAGACAAAAUGCAUACUUUAUAGUUUCAAGAUUUUCAGUAUAUAAAAUCUGUCCAUUCCCAUUAAAAAGUGGAAGAUUUUAAAUAAUUUCUUUACAGAUGUUUUAUUUAAGCAGGUAGCUCAAUCUACUAAUGUUGUUUGAUCUGUGUUUGUUAUACUGGUUGUAAUUAAUUUUUUUAAUUCAUGAACUAGCAGAAAAUUUAUUAAAUUAACUAUUAACUACAUUCACCUUGUAAAUUACUGUAUAAAACUUGUUGACAAUGCACUGACUUUAGAAAGAUGUUAAUGUACAUAAAUAGAGUGUAAAUAAAAUAGUGUUGAUGUACCGAAA